GCUGAGGAGGGUGCCCCGAUGCCGAGGAGGGUGCCCCGAUGCUGAGGAGGGUGCCCCGAUGCCGAGGACGCGGUGCUCUUGGGAGCUCAGCCUCUGCCCCUCUGCAUUCCCGUCAGCAUCCCGGCCCCCAAUCCAUGGCUGGCACGGUGGGGCCUCCAUCCCGCACCUGCACCUACAGAGCCAGCCUGCACCCCAGGCCGGGCCUUGGGGUCUGAGGGAGGCUGACUGCGAGGUGCAGCUGGUGAGUUUUAUGAGACCAAAAUCGAAGAGACAGCCAGCAACAUGAUGGCCAGAGGAGAAGUGCUGUGCAGUGACUUGGUCCCUGCUUCCCAUGGCCAAGUGGCCCAGGAGGAGGAAGGAGAGAAAGCAGGGGGUCUCUGGAGAACUGAAAACUCCCAGAGGACAAGGGCUCCAAUCCCCCUGUGUCGGGGACCAGGCGUGGUGAUGGCUCAAGAGAGGCGCCGUGGUUUCUGCCGGUUCCUCCUGCGUCCCCAGCCUCUCCCCGCCCCUUUCACAACCCCAAAGAGGCUCACAGCUUUGCCACCAGGAGGGCCCCGACCUGGGCCUCCAGCCUUGACCUUCCUCCAGUUGCCAGGCAGUGCCCCCACCCCAGCGGUGCCUGGGAGGGCAGAGUCCCAGGACGGCCCCAGCCACCCACCUUUUCUCGAUCGUUCCUCAGACGCCAGCCCAGGAGCUCUGGGGGGGAUUUUGCAGAUGAAUUUAAGGCCCCAAAUCAGCUAACUUUAAGAUCUUCCUUGGUGGGCUUGACCCACUCAGCUAAGCCCUUAGAAGAGAUGGGGCUCUUCCUGGCAUGAGGGAUCCCAGGUGCAAGAAGGAUUUGACACAAGGGGGUUCUCUGUGUGGCCCCGAAGGAGGCAGAGGCCGCCUGACCAGGACAAGAGCCGCCCCACGGGCAGCCGCCAGGAACCCGGGGCCUCAACACUGCAGCUGGGGGCACAGCUCUGCCAAGCCCCUGGGGGAGCUGGAGAGACUGGGCUCAGGAUCACAGCCCGGCAACCCCUCCACGUGGGCCCAGAGACCCUGAGCAGAGACCCGCAAGCUGAUAAGUGCCUGAGCGUCAAUGGUCUUGGGAACCACACCAAAGCCUCCGUCGGCUCCUCUCCCUCCUGGAAUAUAAGAUGGAGUCCCCUGUGGUACUGCUGCCCCCGCGUCAUAUGCUGCCCCCGCGUCGUAUCCUGCCCACCCCCUGGAGGCAGGCUGCCUCCCCAUCCCCCUGCCUCCCGCCAACCUCGGGGCCUUUGCACAGCCGGCCCUCUCCAUGCAGCGAAUUUCUUCCGCGGGGCUUGUGGCUGGCCCGGCCCCUCAGGCCUUGCUCAGAGGCACGCCCUCGUACAUGCCCUCUCCCUCCUCGCCUGCGCUCUGCUCCGCCCCCUUCGUUACACCACCUCACGUCCUCCCGUGUGUGGCGUGGGUCCCUCCUGAGGGCUGGGUUUGUUCACAGCUGCCUCCCGGCUUCUAGAGGUGCACCCAGCCUCAGAGCCAUGUACUGAGGGCUCAGCCAUGGGCCCAUCUGGGGUGGGACCCUGGCACACCACGCUGUUCUCAGGAUCCAGGUCGUAGCAGCAGUACCACGUCUGAGAAGGAUCAGUGUCGGCUGGCGCUUCUCCUGCAGAUGUGCGCGGAUUUGGAGGAAGCCUGUGGCAGCCUCGGGUGUGUGCGUUGCCAAUCGCCCCGUCCCCUCCUCACCACGUCCAGCACUGCUGUGUCCUGAGGCUGCGCCUGCACUCCGGGUUCCUGCCAUGAAGCCCCCUUUUGUGUCCUCAUGACAAAGGCCAUGCACUGGGGGACCGAAACAACUGGGGCUCGUCUCUCAGGUUCCGUGGGGCUGUGCCCCUUCCGGAGGCUCCUCCUGCUUUGGGGACGCAGGUGUUCCUUGGUGUCCCUUGGCAUCUUCAUGCAGCCGCCUCACCUGUACGUCGGUGUCUCCUCUUCUGCCUCAAAGCCCCUCUGCCUUUCUCCCGGGACACCCGUCACGAGAUUUAGGGCCCACCGUAUAAUCCAUUAUGGUCUCACCCUGAAAACUUUGUUACCUCUGCUGCAAAGACUUCUCCAAACAAAGUCAUGUUUACAGGCUCCUGGGACAGGGAGUGGACGUGCCUUUCAGGGGCCGCCUUGGACUCAGGGUAAAUCUGGCUCAGAGGUUUGCUGUCUUGACAGCUGCCCUCAAGGGGGCUCCCCUCCCGCCCCAGCAUCACCCAUGGGACUCGCUCUCCCUGUCUCGCUCCACUCGAAGGAAACACAGACUCCCCCGCCCGCCACUCCUGCACACUGACCACCAUGGGGCUGGGGUCCAGCUGGGUGAGGCCCCUCAUUGUGACUGGAGCCCACAGGUCGACACCCCAGCCUGUUCCGUGGACUUUUGCUUAAUUCCCUGGUCUUUGGAUGCCUGGAAUGGCUUCCGUGAAGUGCCAGAGCAAAAAACUAAAGAUGUCAGGAAGGAAUGGCUCCGAAUUUUCCUUUUCAAGAGGAGACUGCGUUUCUUUCCACUUGCCCUGCUGAUUUCCCCUCCCUGCGACGUUCGUGCCAGCCCUGUGCUGUCUGCCGCGGAGCCAUGGCUGCCACUGUGACAUGUGCGGUCCCGUCUUCUCCCUCCAUUGUCUGUAGACGCACAGGUGCCACGCAGAACCCUACAGCUCUGUCCAGAUCCUGGAUCCAGAUGAGGCAGCUUUUGAAAGGCGGCCAAGUGAGGGAUGCGUAAACCUCGGGGGCUCCGGACUCCUGUACGUUGCCGCCCAAAGUCAGGACGAGCUGCGGAAGUCACACCUGGACUCUGUGUCUGUCAUCCGCAGACAGCAGCUCCCCAUUCAGCCUGUGUCCCUCGUAAUCCACACCCUCUACUCACAGUGACAUCUGCCCCAAAAGCGCUUCGCUUAACCCUGAAGCUACGAGACCUGCCACCCUACUGUCCCCUCUAGUUUUCUGACAUUUGAGGAACAAGGAAUUGGGUGUAAAAUCAGGAAAUAUCCUACAUGUAAAUUCUUGAUUAUUCUUGUCCUUCCGGGCAGAGCUGCCUCCUGAGUCAUCCGUUUGACUCUUUCUUACUGAAGGCUGAGGGUUGGGGGGUGCAUGGGUGCUCCAAACCCAGAGGCAAUGGCGCGUCCCCUGGCAUGGCAGUCGGAGCAGGCCCCGAGGAGGUCGUGGUCUCAGAACUCAGUCCUUGUGUCAUCCUAGAAAAGAUACUUCAACUUGCUGACCGUCAGCAAGAGCUAAAAACAGGGCGGGAGAAUUUACCACUGAGGAACUUAUGAUCUGAAGUGAAAAACGCAGAGAACAGACUUGCCACCGGUGAAAACCACAAAGCUGAAAUGGAGGCCCUGCCCGGAACGCAGAGGCCACCGCCACUGUGCGUCUCACUCCCUGCAAUGGACGGCGGCCCCCCUCCCACUGCCCAGGCGGCUCUUGGGAAUUUCGUUUUGCUUUUACGGGAAUGUGGCAUGGUCAGCGGUGGCCAUCAGCCAUCCAGGAACCUGGAUUUGACAGGAUUGCUCCAUCCCAUGUCCAGGCAGCCUCAGGUGUGUGGAGACAGGGCAGACUUAGGAGUUCCUCCCCUGGCCUGUGCUCUCCUCCCGGGAAGAACGCUGGAGACCUUCGUCUCUUCUCCUUUCCUCACCUUCCCCAAGCGCUCGCUGCACAAGCCCCCUCCUGCCUUGCCCCUUCUCCCACCCCAUUUCGGUUUUGGUCCCAGCUUACAUCUCGUCCUAAGGAUUAAGUGUUUGUGCAGCUGAGCCGCAGUUCUCAGGUGAGCUGCAGGGCUCCAGCAUGGCACCUGCCUGGGCAGUCCUGAGAGAGGGAUUCGAAGUGGGGAAGGACCCCGGAGUCUCCCUGGCACGUGGUCUGAGGCUCCAGCCACCAGACCCGAAGCUCAGUCUACACUCACCAAGGCCCGACGGCUGCUCCAACCUGGGAGGACCGAUCCGAUCCUGCGCUCCCUGAGGCCGAUGGCUUUUUGACACCCAGGCUUCAGCCACAGACAGACAGACGUUCCCUGCCCGUGGGGGUUUGCCCUUGCUGGAGAGAAACAGAAAUGGACAGAAGGUCACUGGGGUGGCCCUGGGUGUUCUGCGGAGAAUCAAAGUCAUGAGACGGAGACAGGAAUCCCGUUAGGUUUGGGCAGAGUCGCACGUGCUCCUUUCUGGACCUGCUUCAAGGAAUCCGAUGGUUUCACGACAUCCAACCAGUUGCUAUAGGAUAAAUGUUUGUGUCCCUCCAAACUCAGAUGUUGAAACCCUAACCCCAGAGGUGAUGUUUGGGGAGGUGAGGCCUUUGGGAGGAGAUUAGGUCAUGAAGGUGGAGCUCCCAGGUGGGAUCAGAGCCUUUAUAAGGGGCUGAAGAGACCAGAUCUCCUUCCGCAGCAUGGCCAUGCCUCAAGGAGACCUCUGAAUGGGGAAGCCGCCGUCACCAGACACCAAGUCUAUGGGCACCUUCAUCUUGGACUUACCUGGCCAGAGCUGUGAGAUAAAUUUCUGUUGUUUGGGCCUCCCGGCCUAUGGUGGUUUGUUACGGCCGCCCAGACAGACCAACAAACAGCCUGUGUGAAAAUGCGAGCCAUAAACGAGUGGUGUUGACAAAGGCAUCCUGUCCAGGUGGGCGGGGGCAGGACGGAAGCCCGGUUAUCACCUUCCCUGACUACCCGGCCUUCAGCGAGAUUCCGGACAAGGAGUUCCAGAAUGUCAUGACCUACCUCACCAGCAUCCCCAGCCUGCAGGACGCUGGCAUCGGAUUCAUCCUGGUGAUAGACCGGCGACGGGACAAAUGGACCUCCGUGAAGGCGUCCGUCCUGCGCAUCGCAGCAUCUUUCCCGGCAAACCUGCAGCUCGUCCUCGUGCUUCGCCCGACGGGUUUUUUCCAAAGGACUCUCUCCGACAUCGCUUUCAAAUUCAAUAGAGAUGACUUUAAGAUGAAGGUGCCGGUCAUAAUGCUGAGCUCCGUACCAGACUUACACGGUUACAUCGAUAAGUCGCAGCUGACCGAGGACCUGGGUGGGACCCUGGACUACUGCCACUCCCGGUGGCUGUGCCAGCGCACGGCCAUCGAAAGUUUCGCCCUCAUGGUGAAGCAGACGGCUCAGAUGCUGCAGUCCUUCGGGACCGAGCUGGCUGAAACAGAGCUGCCCAAUGACGUCCAGUCGACAAGCUCAGUGCUGUGUGCGCACACAGAGAAGAAGGACAAGGCGAAGGAGGAUUUGAGGCUGGCACUGAAAGAGGGGCACAGUGUCCUGGAGAGCCUCAGGGAGCUGCAGGCUGAGGGCUCAGAGCCCAGUGUGAACCAGGACCAGCUUGACAACCAGGCCACCGUGCAGAGGCUCCUGGCCCAGCUGAACGAAACCGAGGCUGCCUUCGAUGAGUUCUGGGCAAAGCAUCAGCAGAAACUGGAGCAGUGUCUGCAGCUCCGGCACUUUGAGCAGGGCUUCCGGGAGGUCAAAGCCAUCUUGGACGCAGCGUCCCAGAAGAUAGCAACCUUCACAGACAUCGGCAACAGCCUGGCGCAUGUGGAGCACCUGCUGAGGGACCUGGCCAGCUUCGAGGAGAAAUCAGGCGUGGCCGUGGAGAGGGCCCGGGCCCUGUCUCUGGACGGCGAGCAGCUCAUUGGGAACAAGCACUACGCGGUAGACUCCAUCCGCCCAAAGUGCCAGGAGCUCCGGCACCUCUGUGACCAGUUCUCUGCGGAGAUCGCAAGGAGGAGGGGGCUGCUCAGCAAGUCCCUGGAGCUGCACCGCCGCCUGGAGACGUCCAUGAAGUGGUGUGAUGAAGGGAUUUACCUGCUGGCCUCACAACCUGUGGACAAGUGCCAGUCCCAGGACGGCGCGGAGGCUGCCCUCCAGGAAAUCGAGAAGUUUUUGGAGACCGGUGCGGAAAAUAAGAUCCAGGAGCUCAACGCGAUUUACAAGGAAUACGAAUCCAUCCUCAACCAAGAUCUCAUGGAGCACGUGCGAAAGGUCUUCCAGAAGCAGGCAAGCAUGGAGGAGGUGUUCCACCGCAGGCAGGCCAGCCUGAAGAAGCUGGCGGCCAGGCAGACGCGGCCCGUGCAGCCGGUGGCCCCCAGACCCGAGGCACUGGCAAAGUCGCCCUGCCCCUCCCCAGGCAUUCGGCGAGGCUCUGAGAACUCCAGCUCCGAGGGCGGUGCGCUCCGGAGAGGGCCCUACCGGAGGGCCAAGAGUGAGAUGAGUGAGAGCCGGCAGGGCCGCGGCUCAGCGGGGGAGGAGGAGGAAAGCCUGGCCAUCCUGCGCAGGCACGUGAUGAGCGAGCUCCUGGACACAGAACGGGCCUACGUGGAGGAGCUGCUGUGCGUCCUGGAGGGCUACGCCGCGGAGAUGGAUAACCCACUGAUGGCUCACCUCCUGUCAACAGGCCUUCACAACAAGAAGGAUGUUUUGUUUGGAAACAUGGAGGAAAUCUAUCACUUCCACAACAGGAUAUUCCUCAGGGAGCUGGAAAACUACACUGACUGCCCAGAACUGGUUGGAAGAUGCUUUCUGGAGAGGAUGGAAGAUUUCCAGAUCUAUGAGAAGUACUGUCAGAACAAGCCCCGCUCUGAGAGCCUGUGGAGACAGUGCUCCGACUGCCCGUUUUUCCAGGAAUGCCAGAGAAAGCUGGACCACAAGCUGAGCCUGGACUCCUACCUGCUGAAGCCAGUGCAGAGGAUCACCAAGUACCAGCUGCUGCUCAAGGAAAUGCUGAAAUACAGCAGGAACUGCGAGGGGGCUGAGGACCUGCAGGAGGCGCUGAGCUCCAUCCUGGGCAUCCUGAAGGCCGUGAACGACUCCAUGCACCUCAUCGCUAUCACCGGCUAUGACGGGAAUCUCGGCGACCUGGGCAAGCUGCUGAUGCAGGGCUCGUUCAGCGUCUGGACCGACCACAAGAGGGGCCACACCAAGGUGAAGGAGCUGGCCAGGUUCAAGCCCAUGCAGCGGCACCUGUUCCUGCACGAGAAGGCAGUGCUCUUCUGCAAGAAGAGGGAGGAGAAUGGGGAGGGGUAUGAGAAAGCUCCCUCCUACAGCUACAAGCAGUCCUUAAACAUGGCUGCCGUUGGCAUUACGGAGAACGUGAAGGGAGAUGCUAAGAAGUUCGAGAUCUGGUACAACGCGCGCGAGGAGGUCUACAUCGUCCAGGCGCCAACUCCUGAGAUUAAAGCCGCGUGGGUGAAUGAAAUUCGGAAAGUGCUGACCAGCCAGCUGCAGGCUUGUAGAGAAGCCAGCCAGCACCGGGCGCUGGAGCAGUCACAGAGCCUGCCCCUGCCGGCCCCGACCAGCACCAGUCCCUCAAGAGGAAACUCAAGGAACAUCAAGAAGCUGGAAGAAAGGAAAACAGACCCCCUAAGCCUGGAGGGAUACGUCAGCUCAGCGCCACUGACAAAGCCCCCCGAAAAGGGCAAAGGUUGGAGCAAAACGUCCCACUCACUGGAGGCACCUGAGGACGACGGGGGCUGGUCAAGUGCAGAGGAGCAGAUUAACUCGUCCGACGCAGAGGAGGACGGCGGGUUGGGCCCCAAGAAGCUGGUUCCAGGUAAAUACACGGUCGUGGCGGACCACGAGAAGGGAGGCCCCGAUGCGCUGCGCGUGAGGAGCGGGGACGUGGUGGAGCUGGUGCAGGAGGGCGACGAGGGCCUCUGGUACGUCAGGGACCCGACCACUGGCAAGGAGGGCUGGGUGCCGGCCAGCAGCCUGUCCGUCCGGCUCGGCCCGUCCGGCUCGGCCCAGUGCCUGAGCAGCUCAGAGUCGAGCCCGGGGUCGGCCGUGCUGAGCAACUCGUCCAGCUGCAGCGAGGGCGGCCAGGCCCCCUUCUCCGACCUGCAGGGGUAGCGCGGCCUCGGCGCCGGAGACCCGCGCGCUGUCUGGGGCUGCGGUGGCGUGGGGAGGGCGCGGCCCCCGGACGCCCCGAGGAAGGGGCACCUCACCGCCCCCACCCAGAGCGCCUGGCCGUGCGGGCUGCAGAGGACCCCUCCGGGGCAGAGGCAGGUUCCACGGAAGACCCCGGCCCGCUGGGGCUUCCCCGGAGACUCCAGAGCCCACAGAGGAGGGGCCGCAGGGAACAGCCCCGGGCGGCAGGCGCCGGGCAGCGGCAUCUCGUCCUGGCUCCACCGUGCUGCUUCUGCCUCUGGACGGUGCUUUCAGGGGACGCGCGGACCGUGGUGGAGCUGCUUCCGGAGAAGUGGAGGAUCCUCUGGCCAACGGCCUGAGGAGAGCGGGGCACGGGGUCUCUUUAGCUUUUACAAGUUUUAGGAUUUUUUCAAGCAGGGAUCAAUCCCGUGGCCAUUUUUUGUGGUACUUUGGCCUCAAUUCUUCACCAGGAAUCACUGUGUUUACAUGAAAUGACAAUUUGAUACUGUAUUUGAUAGAAAACUAUUUUUUUGUUACCGGGGUUUACAUAGAAGCACGUUGUUUAUACCACUAAGUGACUUUGGGGGGGCUCUCCCAUGGAAACGGAUGGCACUCCCUGAAGCUCCCUGGUCACAGGUGGAUGAAAACGUGUCCGUGGGUGACAUCAGGUGGUGUCUCCACCACCAAAAGCAGUUAGAAGCCAAGGAGAUUCCUUUAUCUACCUAGGGUUCAUUUUCAAAAGAAAAUUUAAACUAUAAUUUAAACAAUUAACGUUCUUUUCUACAAAAAAAAUGCAGGGACUUGAUUUUUUUAAAGAGCUUCACUGAAUUAGGAUAUUUUUAUUGCUUUUAAAGAAAAUACAAAGAUGCAGUUUCUGCAGGGUGUGGCGUGGACCAGUGCUGCCGACCAUAGCUCAGAGAGCCCUGCCCCUGCCUCACUGCACUGCAGCCUCCUCGGAGGCCGCACCUCCACUCCACUCCCCACGCGCCCCCUGCCUCCCACCCAGGUCCACCUGCCACCUGGUGACCACCUUGAGUACAGAAGUGAAAGUGGGGAGAGUAUUUUAUUCAAGUCACAGCAGAACUGGAAAAAAACUCUUCUGUUUUACCAACUUCUUGUGUUUCAGAAACAUAUUCUGUUCAAAACUUUUGAAGCCCUUUCGGUGUCUAGUCUGCAGAUGUUUUUGUAUGUGUGCACCUCUGACCAUGUGUGUACAUAUGUGUCUUGCUGGAAAGGACAUAUUCGCUGUCCCCGUGCUGCUGGGAGGGCCGCCUCACAGCCUCACGGUUCCCAGCCCCAGCACAGUGGAGGCAGGCGUGGCUGCAUUCCCCUCACGCUACCCUCCCAGCGGCUUGUAGCCGUCACUGGCCAGACCUCCAGGGUGCGGAAUCAAAUAGGAAGCAUGCAGAGACUCGGCAGCUUUUCCUCUGAUGUGUAAGUUAUUUGGAACGCGUGCUGUGUCCCGCGAUGUCCCUGAUGUACUGUGCAGGCGCGGUGCCUCCGUCUCGUCGCACAGCUGCGCGCCCUUGUGUGACCCUCCCCAUAAAGGCACUUUACAGCUUCAUGUUUCAUCCACUGUCACUUUUUUUUAACUGCUGAUGUAAAUGGAAUUUUAAAAGCAGAGUUCUUUAUUGUAUGGAUGACGUUUGAAUAAAUAUCAGCAACUCCUGCCAUCUGCCUUUGUCUGUCAAGACACAGAACGUCUCAGCAGUCGGGGUUUCCAGGGCCGCAGUGCACUGUGCUUGCACAUGGUAAGUCAUUGUUGGGACGGAAAAGAAGCCGGCAGUGGGCAGGGCCCAGCGUGCGGCUCAGGCACCGAGCAACCGCUUUGCUUUCUUCUGUCAGACGGCGAUGAUGACAAAAUAGCAACAAGGUUGUGCGUGUCAGAAACGCAAAGGCAGCAGAGGAAGCGUAGUGGAACCAUUACAGAAUCACAAUGCAGCCGACACUCUCCAGACCAGAAAAGGGAGCAUAAAGAAAGGGUAUUGAUCCAAUAGAAGAAGGGAAGGGUGGAGAAAGGGGAAAGCAUGGUUAACAGGAAACAACAUGUAACGGAAGAGACAGCCCAGAUGUGUCUGGCUCACAACAGACGUGAUCAUGUUAUGCUGGCCUGGAAGAGCAUCGGAUCAGACGUGACAAGUCACUGCUUAGAGACCAUCAAGCAAAUUUAUAUAUAGAUUGGAGAUUUAAAAUAAAAGAAGACAGAACAGACAAACACCAUAAGAAAGCUGGUGUAGCAGUAUCGAUGACCUGAAAUGGGAUUCAGGACAGUUCAUAGAGUAAAGGGGGCUGCGUGGCAAUCAGGAACUCAUAAGCCACUGACUAUAAAGCUCAAAACACAGCAAAGUUGGCAGUCGGCAGACAGCAAUGUUGACUGUCAUGAAAAGUGAUCCCUGUUUGCCCCUAAACGUAGAGAAAUCUGCGUUAUUUUCCAGCACACAUGGAGCACAAACAAAAUAUUUGCAAAACAAUGGGAAGAUCAUUGAAACACUGUUUGGCAAUUUAAAAGCUUGUUUCUAACUCACGGGAUGCGGGCAGUCUGCUCUCUAGAACUGGACAGCGUGCACAGAGCCACGGGAGGGAGCAGCCACGGCCAGCUCAGAUUGGUGUCGACAGCUUAGUGGUGUCUGAUUUUAUACAUGACAAAAUGAACGAGUUAACCAUUUAAGCCAAAAAAAUAAGACUAGCGUAACCCAAAGAAAGUAUUUAAAUACUUCUGUCAAUUAGGACAGUUGAGAAAAGAGAAUAACAAAAUCAAAAGCAAAACUCAAACUUUGUACCUGAAAAAUCUAAUAAAACUGACUAAUUUAUAGAAAACCUAAGAAACUCCAUAUCAAAUAAAAAAUUUUAAAUAUGAGAGAACCA